AGACUCAGUGCUCCCUCCUCCUCCCGCGCCCCGCGCUCUGCGCGCUGAGCUGGCGCCGGGCUCCGCUUGCACAGCACCGGGACCGACGGGCACUGCUGGGAGAGCCGCUCUCCCAGGUUCCACCUCCCCGAUGCAGAGUCCGUGGGGGAAACCAGGCUUUCCUCCCAGAACCAAGGGAGCGAGCCGAGGGGGCAGCUGCUGUGGGGGCUUCUGAGGAGACAGCCUGGCUUCUUUCCCUACUUCCUGGAGAGGGCAGGAAACCUCAGAAUAGAGGAACGCUGCUCCCUGGUCAGCAAGCAGCCCCCAACCUGGAUGGAGUGAAACAUGCGGCCUGAUGACAUUAACCCGAGGACUGGGCUGGUGGUGGCCCUGGUCAGUGUCUUCCUCGUCUUUGGUUUCAUGUUCACCGUCUCUGGGAUGAAAGGGGAGACUUUGGGAAACAUCCCCCUCCUGGCCAUCGGGCCAGCCAUCUGCCUACCAGGCAUCGCAGCCAUUGCCCUGGCCAGGAAAACCGAGGGAUGCACCAAGUGGCCAGAGAACGAGCUGCUGUGGGUCCGCAAAUUGCCCUGCUUCCGGAAACCCAAAGACAAGGAGGUGGUAGAGCUGCUGAGGACCCCUUCAGACCUAGAAUCCGGCAAGGGGAGCUCAGAUGAGCUGGCUAAGAAGGCGGGCCUCAGGGGGAAGCCUCCCCCACAAAGCCAGGGUGAGGUGUCCGUGGCCAGCUCCAUCAACAGCCCCACACCCACGGAGGAAGGAGAAUGCCAGAGCCUCGUCCAGAAUGGGCAUCAGGAGGAGACGUCCAGAUACCUGGACGGCUACUGCCCCUCGGGCAGUUCCCUCACCUACAGUGCCUUGGACGUCAAGUGCUCAGCAAGGGACAGAUCUGAGUGCCCUGAGCCUGAGGAUAGCAUCUUCUUUGUGCCCCAGGACAGUAUCAUCGUUUGCUCCUACAAGCAGAACAGCCCGUAUGACAGAUACUGUUGUUAUAUCAAUCAGAUACAAGGCAGGUGGGACCACGAGACCAUCGUCUAAUCUCUGCCUACAAAGGUGGCUGGAUUGAUAGAAUAUGACUAAGCCCAGCUCCCCGUGGAAGCAAAUUGCUCUGCUUGGAGAGCCUUCACACUGUUAGAAAUUGACCUGGUAUGUGAUGGGUGUGAUAACCUCUGGUACCCGAGAGUCAUGUAAAUAGGCAUGUUGGGGACACAUUUUAGGGAAGGGCGAUGAGGGUUAAGGACACUGGAAGAGGCAGUGGGUAGGAAAGGAAGCUACUCCAGUUGCUUCUUAACAAUUUACACAAUGUUAAAUGUUUUGUAAAAUAACCCAAAAAGUGCUAUCCAGAACCAGCUGAGAGCAAGAUAAAUCUAGAGUGGGCUGCAGAUGUGAGGCAUCAAAUGAUGCAUGAGCUGACCACAGGGAAACUGAGCUGCUUUAUGUUUGAAUAAGUUGAAAAUAAAAUUAAUGAUCCGUUAUAUAAAGUAAUUUUUGCCUGGUUAAAAGCUUAUCACACUUGGUAUUUGCUGAAAGAAAAAAAAAUCAAGAUACAAGAGUUAAACCCUCCUUAGAUGGGAUGGUUUUUGGGAAAAGGGUAGUUAAAGAGAGUUGGAUUAUGUAACUGAGUCUUGUGGCAUUAUUGUCUGACAAGAUCAUGGUCUCUAAUAAAGUAAAAUAAGUGUGAGCAGCUAUGUGAAAAGUUAACAUUUUUAGAUGGCUAUGUUACUUCUUAAACUCUUCGUUUAAAUCCAUUUAUUGCAUCUUUAUCUGAAAUGGGUUUUUUCUAAACAUUUACUAUCAUUCAUGUAUUAUUUCCUUACCAGGUGCAACAUUAUUUGAAAUGAUACUUUCAUAGAUUGGAAUUUGUUUUCAUCAAGACAAAAUGAAUUUUACAUAUAUAUCCAAGUCUUUAACAUUGGCAGACAUGUACUGAUAAUUACCAUUCCUACAUACCUUUUAAAAUCUGAAAACUAUAAAGUCUACACAUUAGCCUUGAACAUUGCACAUAAUUUGUAUGAAAUGCAAUGGUUAAACCUUUGGAAGUGUCAUUAUUUGUACAUUUGUUCAACUCCUCUCACAGACUGUAAAUGCCAGUGAAACAAGAACUCAUCUACUAAAUUUAACUGAAGCCUAGAUUUUAUUAAGCUCACCUGAUCAGUGAACAUUACAUGAUAAAAGUCUCUUUAUUUCAUACAUUUUUGCUGCUGAGGAAAACAACAAAUCACAAUGAUAUCCUAAAAUGUGCUUUCUAUUUCACUUGCUCAACUGCAAUAGAUAAGAAGGCUAUCAAGCAGAAUGCCAUUUGAUCCCCGGUGAAGAAAAAUAUGAAUUAUAUAUAGGAAUGGUGAUAGAGUUCAUCUUGAAGAUCAGAAGUAUUUUGUAUCCUUCAAAGAAUGAUCAUUUUAAGUGAUCAUAUAGUCUUAGUCACUUUCUCCCAAAAGGGGAAUUGAGGACAAAAAUUUGGGCAUAUAUGUUUUGUGUAUUUCAAUUCCAACUCUGCAAUUCUUUCUUAAGUAUAGCAAUUGUUCUGUCUUAAGAAUCAUGGUAUUUUUAAAAAAUCAUAAUUUUCAAGUCAAGUUCAAGAUCAAAAAUAUGUAAUUAUUUUAGUAGGGCUUAAAUAUCAGAAAUGAGAUGCAUGAUCUUGGGCAAAUUUUAUCUUCUUACACCUGAGUUUCCUACUCUGUGAAGGGAGGGGGAACUGAUUUACACUUGAUUAUUUCUAUCAUUCAUUUUCAGUGUAAAUAUUCUAUGGUGUUAUGUCAAAGGCAUUUUAUAUAUUGCCAGGAAAUGAGUUACAGCAAAAUGCAUGCCAAAGUUAUGAAAUUUAUGAUAAUUAUGUGACAUACAUUGCACAGCUACUACUCAAAAAAGAAUUUUGUAGAUGUAUGAAAGCAGAUUAUUCAACACAAUGCAUUCCUGAGAAUAAAAUGAACAUAAUCAGAGUAAAAUAUUUUUGAGGAGAAAACUUAAAAUGUUGGUAUAACUCAAAGUAAUCUAAUACACAACCUUGCACUAAAUGUGAUUGACAUUUGGAUUUGGGAUGGGGAGAGAUAGUUUCCUAAAAUCACAGUAACUUUUAAUAAUUGUAAUGCAUUUUGAAAACAGAGAAUCAUAUUUUUAUAAUGGUGAGAACUAUGCAAUAACUCUUUAGGAAUGAAAACUUCCUUUAAGAAGUUUGCCACCGUUAGAGAUGAGGAGAUAGUGAGACAGAGAGAUGUUCACAGAGACUCAGCAAAUCUUAGACAAUAAUGCUGCAAUUUUCUGAAAGAAGAUGCUUGCAGUGUCAGGUAUGGUUUGGGGGUUGGAAAAGUUACUUUUCUGAUUUCUUGGAACCAUUUAAAACUCCUUUAUAUCAUUCUGUCUCUUUCCAAAUUGAGGGUCAACUACUAGUUUAGAGAUAUAAGGUAUUUUAUCUUGUUUUCAAGUUCUACUUCAGAAGAAAACCUAUUUCAUGUUUCUUCUCCCAUUACCUACUUAAGAUACUUAAGGUAUUUAAGUAUGCAUUUGAGGAAAUAUUUUCCUGUGCUAAAAUAAAGGUUUGCAAAUGUUGGUGUGAGAGGUUUUAACUUUGACCAGUGAGAAUAAAAUGUAUGAUUGUGUGUGUGAAUUUCUCCUAACAUAUUAACCAACUCCUUUCUAUAUGCAACAAGGUAACCUGGUGCCCCAAAUCAAUACUUGUAAGUACUAUUCAGAGUUAAACUUCCAAAGUCAAAAAAUAUAUAUACACAAAAAAAGGGGAAAAGCCACAUUUUUUUGAACAGAGGUAGAAGAGAAAGAGAAAAAAAGUGUCUCAGCCCUUUAGAGGAAAAGAGAGCAACUCAUUCUGAUGAGUUACACAGUUUUAGCAAAUUGUUCUUAUCAAUAUAAUAGACAUGAGGAUUGUUCCUGGUAGCCUUCAAGAGCUCCUAGACAGAUAUAAAUUUAAGUAGACAUUACUUUAUUUUGCUGUUAAUCCAAGUAGACAUUGCGACUUGAUUCUGAAUAGGCAUUUUAUUUUCAAAAUUUUUCUACUGAAUUUCUCUUGCUCUGUAUGCCUACUUAUUGUGCACAUGGGUUGUUUUUCCAAACUGCUUCUUGAUUCUUAAGUGAGAAUUCAGACAUGAUACUCAAACGAGAGCAUAUUAGACAUCUGUUUUAAGAUUUAUUUUCUGUUGCAGUCAUCUUGGCAAACAAAAUCCAGAUACAGUUAAGUUCAGGCUCUCUUCCAAACCCUGCUAAGCAGCUGCUUUGAAAAUGUUUUCAAUACUAUGGAUCUUAAUAUCCACUGAGAUGACAAAUGUAGGAAAGGAAGAUUCAUUCUGUUAAAUGUUUUUUCUCUUUUGCAAUGUCCAAGCUCUACUUAUUUAUUAAUAGCCUCCCUCUGUACCCAUAACAUCAUUUAUUUGGUGAAUUCACUGUUAUUAAUACUAGUAUUUUAUCACAGUAAAGAAAAGGUUUCUGAAAACCCACAACCUCACUAUCCUAAAGCAACUACUGUGUUUCUAUUUUGGUAUAUCAUCUUCCAGGCUUCCUCCACAUGCAAAUGCAGCAUACAUAUUAUAAUAGUGUGUUUUUCUUUUCUCUUUGAAUUAUAUUCCAUGCAUGUUUCCAUGUUUCUAUGUAGUAUUUCUAAUUAUCAAUGAACGAUUGUGUAAUAUGCCAUUUUAGUGAUGUUCCAUAAUUUAUCAUGCCAUUCCUUAUUGCUGGCAAGAUACUAAGUUUUAUGGAUGAUUUUGUAUGUUUUUUUCCUAUUGCUGGUUACACUGCUAUAUUAUUUGUUAUAUGCCAAUAGAGAGGAACUUUACUAUUGAACAGGUAUCUCCUUGUGGAUGAGAGAGAGGAGGCAGAAAUGUGUAAAUGAAUGGAACUCUCCAUAUUGUUGUGUGGGUCUUCCCUUCACUCUUGUGGAUAUAAGACCCAGGGUGGGAAACAAAACGAUGCUUCUUCCAAAAGAUCCUCCCAUCAGGACCAGAACUAGUAUGUUUAGGAGUAAGAUGGAACAUUUCCCCAGCUAAGAUACCAGUGGUGUGUUUCUCACAAUUAGAUUACAGUGGUGUCAGUCUUCAAGAGCAUCGUGUUCAACAAGCAAAAUGAUAAAUAGAUGUAAACAAUAAUAAUGACUUUGUAAUAUGCCAAAAGCAUUUUCUUAAAGUACCUCAUCAUAUAUUUUAUAAUAGAUGUAUUUCAUAUGUAUAUGUAUUGUCGCCUAUCAGUGACUUACAAAUGAACUGGAAUUUCAGGAAUCUGAUAGACUCUGCCCUUGAGUUUUCUGUGUUUCAGUUUCCUACUGGGAAAAACUAAACUGAGGAUGGAAAUGGGGACAAAUGCUUGGUUUGCCCAAAUAUCUUAAUAAAAGACUAGAUUCCAUUCAA